GCAAGAGGAAGAAGAGAAAACGGCCGGGCGGCGGUGGCUGUAGGUUGUGCGGCUGCAGCGGCUCUUCCCUGGGCGGACGAUGGACAGCCAGGGCAGGAAGGUGGUGGUGUGCGACAACGGCACCGGGUUUGUGAAGUGUGGAUAUGCAGGCUCUAACUUUCCAGAACACAUCUUCCCAGCUUUGGUUGGAAGACCUAUUAUCAGAUCAACCACCAAAGUGGGAAACAUUGAAAUCAAGAAUAACAAAAAGAUGGAUCUUAUGGUUGGUGAUGAGGCAAGUGAAUUACGAUCAAUGUUAGAAGUUAACUACCCUAUGGAAAAUGGCAUAGUACGAAAUUGGGAUGACAUGAAACACCUGUGGGACUACACAUUUGGACCAGAGAAACUUAAUAUAGAUACCAGAAAUUGUAAAAUCUUACUCACAGAACCUCCUAUGAACCCAACCAAAAACAGAGAGAAGAUUGUAGAGGUAAUGUUUGAAACUUACCAGUUUUCCGGUGUAUAUGUAGCCAUCCAGGCAGUUCUGACUUUGUACGCUCAAGGUUUAUUGACUGGUGUAGUGGUAGACUCUGGAGAUGGUGUGACUCACAUUUGCCCAGUAUAUGAAGGCUUUUCUCUCCCUCAUCUUACCAGGAGACUGGAUAUUGCUGGGAGGGAUAUAACUAGAUAUCUUAUCAAGCUACUUCUGUUGCGAGGAUACGCCUUCAACCACUCUGCUGAUUUUGAAACGGUUCGCAUGAUUAAAGAAAAACUGUGUUACGUGGGAUAUAAUAUUGAGCAAGAGCAGAAACUGGCCUUAGAAACCACAGUAUUAGUUGAAUCUUAUACACUCCCAGAUGGACGUAUCAUCAAAGUUGGGGGAGAGAGAUUUGAAGCACCAGAAGCUUUAUUUCAGCCUCACUUGAUCAAUGUUGAAGGAGUUGGUGUUGCUGAAUUGCUUUUUAACACAAUUCAGGCAGCUGACAUUGAUACCAGAUCUGAAUUCUACAAACACAUUGUGCUUUCUGGAGGGUCUACUAUGUAUCCUGGCCUGCCAUCACGGUUGGAACGAGAACUUAAACAGCUUUACUUAGAACGAGUUUUGAAGGGUGAUGUGGAAAAACUUUCUAAAUUUAAGAUCCGCAUUGAAGACCCACCCCGCAGAAAGCACAUGGUAUUCCUGGGUGGUGCAGUUCUAGCGGAUAUCAUGAAAGACAAAGACAACUUUUGGAUGACCCGACAAGAGUACCAAGAAAAGGGUGUCCGUGUGCUAGAGAAACUUGGUGUGACUGUUCGAUAAACUCCAAAGCUUGUUCCCGUCAUACCCGUAAUGCUUUCUUUUUUCCUUUAUUGCCAAUCUUUGAACUCAUUCAACUCCAGGACAUGGAAGAGGCCUCUCUCUGCCCUUUGACUGGAAAGGUCAAGUUUUAUUCUGGUGUCUUGGGGAAGCUUUGUUAAAUUUUUGUUAAUGUGGGUAAAUCUGAGUUUAAUUCAACUGCUUCCCUACAUAGACUAGAGGGCUAAGGAUUCUGUCUGCUGCUUUGUUUCUUCUAAGUAGGCAUUUAGAUCAUUCCUAUAGGCUUCCUAUUUUCACUUUACUGCUCUAAUGCUGCUAGUCGUAGUCUUUAGCACACUAGGUGGUAUGCCUUUAUUAGCAUAAAACAAAAAAAACUUUAACAGGAGCUUUUACAUAUUACUGGGAUGGGGGGUGGUUCGGGAUGGGUGGGCAGCUGCUGAACCCUUUAGGGCAUUUCCUCUGUAAUGUGGCGCUUUCAACUGUACUGCUGCAGCUUUAAGUACCUUAAAGCUUCUCCUGUGAACUUCUUAGGGAAAUGUUAGGUUCAGAACUAAAGUGUUUUGGGUGGGUUUUGUUGCGGGGGGGAGGGUAACAAUGGGUGGUCUUCUGAUUUUUAUUUUUGAGGUUUUGUCAACUGGAGUACGUAGAGGAACUUUAUUUACAGUACUUUGAUUUGGCAGGUUUUCUUCUACUUGUGCUCUGCCUGGAGCUGUUUCCAUAUGAUAUAAAAAGCAAGUGUAGUAUUCCAUUACUAUGUGGCUUAGGGAUUUAUUUGUUUUUUAAAAUCAACCAUGUUAGCUGGGAUUAGACUCCCUACAGUCCUUCAAUGGAAAAGUAACAUUUAAAAAUCCUUUGGGUAAUUCGAAUUACAGAUUUAAAAGAGCUUAAGAUCUGGUGUUUUGUUAAUGCUUCUGUUUAUUCCAGAAGCAUUAAGGUAACCCAUUGCCAAGUAUCAUUCUUGCAAAUUAUUCUUUUAUAUAACUGACCAGUGCUUAAUAAAACAAGCAGGUACUUACAAAUAAUUACUGGCAGUAGGUUAUAAUUGGUGGUUUAAAAAUAACAUUGGAAUACAGGACUUGUUGCCAAUUGGGUAAUUUUCAUUAGUUGUUUUGUUUGUUUUGAUUUGAAACCUGGAAAUACAGUAAAAUUUGACUGUUUAAAAUGUUGGCCAAAAAAAUCAAGAUUUAAUUUUUUUAUUUGUACUGAAAAACUAAUCAUAACUGUUAAUUCUCAGCCAUCUUUGAAGCUUGAAAGAAGAGUCUUUGGUAUUUUGUAAACGUUAGCAGACUUUCCUGCCAGUGUCAGAAAAUCCUAUUUAUGAAUCCUGUCGGUAUUCCUUGGUAUCUGAAAAAAAUACCAAAUAGUACCAUACAUGAGUUAUUUCUAAGUUUGAAAAAUAAAAAGAAAUUGCAUCACACUAAUUACAAAAUACAAGUUCUGGAAAAAAUAUUUUUCUUCAUUUUAAAACUUUUUUUUAACUAAUAAUAGCUUUGAAAGAAGAGGCUUAAUUUGGGGGUGGUAACUAAAAUCAAAAGAAAUGAUUGACUUGAGGGUCUCUGUUUGGUAAGAAUACAUCAUUAGCUUAAAUAAGCAGCAGAAGGUUAGUUUUAAUUAUGUAGCUUCUGUUAAUAUUAAGUGUUUUUUGUCUGUUUUACCUCAAUUUGAACAGAUAAGUUUGCCUGCAUGCUGGACAUGCCUCAGAACCCUGAAUAGCCCGUACUAGAUCUUGGGAACAUGGAUCUUAGAGUCACUUUGGAAUAAGUUCUUAUAUAAAUACCCCCAGCCUUUUGAGAACGGGGCUUGUUAAAGGACGCGUAUGUAGGGCCCGUACCUACUGGCAGUUGGGUUCAGGGAAAUGGGAUUGACUUGGCCUUCAGGCUCCUUUGGUCAUAAUUUUAAAAUAUGGGAGUAGAAAACAACAAAGAAUGGAAUGGACUCUUAAAACAAUGAAAGAGCAUUUAUCGUUUGUCCCUUGAAUGUAGAAUUUGUUUUUGAUUUCAUAAUUCUGCUGGUAAAUGUGACAGUUAAAAUGGUGCAUUAUGUAUAUAUAUUAUAAUUUAGAAAUACCAUUUUAUAAUUUUACUAUUCCAGGGUGACAUAAUGCAUUUAAAUUUGGGAUUUGGGUGGAGUAUUAUGUUUAACUGGAGUUGUCAAGUAUGAGUCCCUCAGGAAAAAAAAAAAAUUCUGUUUUAAAAAGCAAUCUGAUUCUUAGCUCUUGAAACUAUUGCUACUUAAAUUUCCAAUAAUUAAAAAUUUAAAAUUUUUAAAUUAGAAUUGCCAAUACUUCUACAUUUGAGAAGGGUUUUUUUAGAAAUACAUUUAGUAAAGUCCCCAAGACAUUAGUCUUACAUUUAAACUUUUUUCUUUAAAACAUGGUUUUGGUGGUUAACUUUUACACAGUUCUGAGUACUGUUAAUAUCUGGAAAGUAUCUUGAGAUAUCAGUGGAAAGCUAAACAGUCUAAAUUAACAUGAAAUACUUCAUUUUGAUUGAGAAAAUAAAAUCAGAUUUUUUCAAAGUCAA